CCGUGCGCUCCUCUCCAGGACCCAGGCAAACACAAAAAAGGAGGCUCAGACAACCAAGCACCCAGGCCCGAACCUCCAACAAGCGUGUCUUGGGAGCGCUGCCCUGCACUUCCCACCCUGCCGGGGUCGCGGCGGUUUUUGUCCUCCUCCGCCGGCUCAGGGAAGACUGGUUAAAUUCCAGGUCAGCCCUACAGAGCCAGGGUUCGCCGGCAAAGAACAAAAAAACAAUUGUCUCCCUUAUAUCCGAGCAAAUAGUCUAGACUGGGGUGUUAAGCCAUUUAUAGAAAAAUCUCCAGGGCGCGCUCAGCCUCGUGGUCUUGUCAAUCACAGACGCACAAUAGCAAGCCUGCAAAGGGAACGGGGACGGGCGUGAACCAUUUCCUCCACCAGCAGGGUCCUCCGAUGCCGCAGCAUCCACCCCACACCUUAAACCUCAUGGUAUUAGUGGGCAAUUUAAAAGAUAAAGACACAGGGAAGCGGGACUAAUUGGGAAAACCUGCAGACAUUUGUUUUAAUGCGUAAUCUGCUAAAUAACUACGGGGGUGGGGGUGGGGAAGGAAGAGAUCCAAGGAGGCAGAAGGCUGCGGUCAAAAUAUUUUGGGGUGGCAGAGUCACGUAGGAUGUGGCUGUGGGUUCUGGCAGCCCAGAGAUUCAGCUCCCGCCUCCUCCCUCAGAGCGAGUCCAUAGCUACCCUCACGUCCCCCGUGGCGGUCCUCGCCACGCUCCGGAGCGGGUUACCCAUGAGGGUGCUAGACCUGGGCAGCGGGAACCUCGAAGAGGUGGAGAUUGCAGGCUGGGACUCCAGAUUUCGGGCAGGGAUGCGGGGAAGGGAAGACGCCUCGCUGGAGGCGGAAUGGAGGGCAAGGCGAAGGAGGAUGGUGCAGGAAACGGCGACAAGGCGCCCGGCCAGGCCCGCGAGCUACCGAGACCCGGGUUCCAAUCCUCCCCCCUUCCGCAAACGCCCGGGUUCGAGGUACCUGGCGGGCAAGGGCCGCAGCGGAGCGAAGCGGGCUGGCCAUGGGGAGGCUGCGGGGACGCGGGGCUGCAGAGAGCGGCAGUGGCACGGAGCGCGCGGCUGGAAGCGAAAGCAGGCGGUGUGGCCAAGCCCCGGCGCACGGCCCAUAGGGCGCUGGGUACCACGACCUGGGGCCGCGCGCCAGGGCCAGGCGCAGGGUACGACGCAACCCCUCCAGCAUCCCUUGGGGAGGAGCCUCCAACCGUCUCGUCCCAGUCUGUCUGCAGUCGCUAAAACCGAAGCGGUUGUCCCUGUCACCGGGGUCGCUUGCGGAGGCCCGAGAAUGCGCGCCACGAACGAGCGCCUUUCCAAGCGCAGAUAUUUCGCGAGCAUCCUUGUUUAUUAAACAACCUCUAGGUGAAUGGCCGGGAAGCGCCCCUCGGUCAAGGCUAAGGAAACCUCGGAGAAACUACAUUAGGGCAGCUUUUCCACCGACUCCAAAUCCAACUGACAAAAAGCAGUUUCUGCCCUCGAGAGUUUGCGGGCGGGGAUUGACAUUUGUGCGUCUGCUCUUGUCUGCCACUGACCGCUAUGUGCAAACUGAAGGGGGAGAACGUGAAUCCAGCUUUUAGAUUUCCCUGCGCCACCUACCCAAACCGAAUUUGUAACUCGGGGUGUUAUGGGGCUACCAGGCUCGCAUUCCCUAAGGGCCAUUUCUGCCCAAAGAUCUCAAUGCCUUUCAUCGUUUUCAGGCAAAGCAGACCAUCAAGAGCUCCAAUCAUACUGUUUUCAUAGUUUUCCGAUGUAGGCUCGUGAUCGCAAUAUUUAGAAAGAGGACUGGAAAAGUGAUGUUAGAAGUACUAUUCGGUUUAGAAAGGGAAAGGAGGAUUGGAAUAGCUAUUGUCUUAUAUGCAGUGUUCGCCUGGGGCAACGUCAGCCUAAAUUAUGAGCCUUCCUGGUUUUUAAAUUAAUAGGAAGUGGUAACUGGGGCUGACUUGAUCUUGGAAAGAGGGGGAGGGCAGUUUAUUCUGGGUGAAAGCGGUUAAAUCCGGUUUGGUUUUUUAAAUGGUUUCAUACAACGCUACUGAUAAUAUACUGUAGCUCUAAUCUUAUCAACUCAGAAAACCUACACUUUUCCUCUCCUUUAUACAAGGCACAGAAAGGCCUCUUACGCUGGGGUGGGGUCCCAAGCUCCAAAGACCACAGAGUCCAGGCAGGUCACGUACCACCAUAGAGCGGCGAGUGUCCCUGGAAGUCCAGGGUCGCUUAUAAGAUAAGUUUUGUCCUUGUUGUUUUGAGACGGAGUCUCGCUCUGUCGCCCAGGCUGGAGUGCAGUGGCGCGAUCUCGUCUAAUUGCAACAUCCGCCUCCCCGGUUCAAGCAAUUCUCCCAUCUCAGCCUCCCCAGUAGCCGGGACUACAGGCCUGCGCCACCACGCCGGGCUAAUUUUUGUAUUUUUUGUAGAGACCGGGUUUUGCUAUGUUGCCCAGGCUGCUCUCAAACUCCUGGACUCAAGCCACCCACCUAUCUCAGCCUCCCAAAGUGCUAGGAUUACAGGCGUGAGCCACGGCGCCCGGCCUCCAUCUGUAUUAACUGCUUCUAUUUCCUCCCCAUUAAGGGCUUCUGUCCAAUUAUUCCACCUAAAUAAGGUCUCUAAUAGCCUUCAUUUUGUUCCUGCCAAUGGUUUUGCUUCUCGUGCAUUUUCAUGGCUGCACCUAUGUGCUGAUGACUCCCAAAUAUAUUUUUUCAGUCCAUCUGUCUCCUGAGCAGUAGGUACUUGCUACUCAAAAAUCUGUCUAAAAUAAAAACGGUGUAUCUAUCCACCAUGUUCGAAGCACUGGGCUAGUUGCUGGGGGAGGGUUGAGAGCAUACCAUCAUCCUGUUAUCAUGCAUUGCCCCCAGCCAGAGAGAAAAGUGUUAAUUGUGUUAGAAAGUGUUAAGGAAUCCCACAGACAGAUGUAAAAUUAUAACAAGUGCUGCCUGUGCUCUAAGAGCCUCUAAUAAUGGAUUGUAUUGACUCAGAAAGGCCUGGAAAGGCUUUCAGCAAGUGAUCCUUGAGCAGAAAUCUGAAAGAUUAAAGAAAUUUACUAAAGGAAGAAGGGAUGAAGAGCACCUGGUAUGAAAGUGAGUUCCAGGACAAAAGAACUUCUCUGAGGAGGGCUGGAACAAAGGGCCAAAAGAGAGCCUGGGGCUGCGGUAGACAGAAGAGGAUGGAGCUUGGGCUAGUGAGUAGCCAAAGGGCCAGCCAAGUAGUGCCUUAGGGAGAGCUAAAGAAUAAUUUUAAAAAGCAAAAAUAAGGUAAAAGCCUGACUGUCAUACAGGUAUAAAAUAAACUAAAUUAUAGAGUUUAUUUAAAUCAUUUAAUGAAGUUACCAGGCAGAUAUAAAAACUGGUUCAAAGAACAGGCAUGUUUAUAGGUCAGAAAUAUUGAAAUGAAUAUGCAAAUGAAAUUGGCUUCUUCCACAGUAGGGGAGAGAAGUUAAUUGAACCCUGACCUUCAGAUUUUACUUGCAUGACUGCAUGCAAUAAUUAUUUUGCAUUUCUAUCAGUCAUCUGUAAAAUAACUCAAAAACAAUGAAACAAUGUAAGACCCAAUGAAAGGGCCCAUGGAAUCAGAAUCAGAUAACCUUAAAGGUUUGCUCUAAAUAAUUCAGUUUUCCAUUGAAGUACAAAUUUUUCCCUACAGUACGGUAAUAUAAUUUCUUCAUUCAAGAAGUGCUAUUAGUCAGCAACAGCUGAAGUAAACCAGACAUAGUAGUCACUGUACUUACUAGUUACACUAAGAAGCUGUAGCUUUAGCAGUUUUCAAUUUAGCUUAACCUAGGGGCAAGAGAAACCAUUGAAAGGUUAAGGAUUAGGUGGAGUAUGCAGGAGCGGUGACAGAAUUGAAGGUAUUGGCUGCAGUUUGGAGAUUGGAAGAGGGUCUGGGUGGAGAGGAAUGGAUUUUGAAGAAGCUAUUACAGAACCCACAUACGAGAUGAUCCUUUUAAUAAGUCAGAUUUGGCUGGUGGUUGGUAAUAGAAGUGGAGAGAAACAGCCAGAUUUCAGCAAGAAUGGAGAUAAGGUGGCAGCCUGGGCAACAUGGCAAAACCCUGUCUCUGGUAAAAAUACAAAAAUUAGCCGGGCUCGGUGGCAUGUGCCUGUAGUCCCAGCUACUCACGGGAUUAAGGUGAGAGGAUUACCUGAACUUGGUGAGGUUGAGGCUGCAGUGGGCCAGGAUCACACCACUGCACUUGCCUGGGUGACACAGUGAGACACCAUCUCAAAAAAAAAGAAAAAGAAAAAUAGAUGAUAUAAGGUGGGACAAGGAUGAGAGAAGUGCCAAGGAGGCCUCCUUGGAUCUGACUUGCUUAUCUAUUUGGUGAUGUUCACUAAGAAAAAAGGAAUGUUGAAAAAGAAUGUGUUUGAGGGGAUGAGGAGGAGUCUGGUUUGGGACCUAUGAUUUCUGAAGUGUCUCCAAGACUGGCUGUGAGAGAUCUGCCUGUCUGAAGCUCAGAGAAGAGGUCUGGAUUAGAGGUAUUAUUGAAUCAUUGGCAUAGAGGUGGUAACUGAAGCUAUGGGUGCGAAAGAGAAUCUCUAUGUCAGUUUUCUCCGCUGUAAAAUGAGACAAUAGCAACACUUCAUGUUUGUCAACUGGGAUAGAUGAGCAUUAAUAUAUGAAACUUAUGUAUAUUACUUAGAACCAUGCCUGAUGUCAGCCAUGCAGAAUAGGUGAAAGAACGGGCAUGGCUCUGUUUCCAUUAAACUGUAUUUGAAAAACGGGACAGAGCAAAUGUGGUCUGUGGACUGUAAGUUGCUUACUCCUGCUCUAUGUAGUUGCUCUAGUAGAAACAUAGCAGUUGUCCCUCAAAUGCAUCCAAGUGAUGAUCACCAAUGUCUAUCCAUUCUUGCUCCAAAUACCCUGACAGUUGCCAUUUCUCCAACCAUGUUAUCCGCAUCCUAGUACCAAACAGCUUCCAAGCAGCUCCUCUGACCCCAGCCUUGCUUCUCUUUAAGCCAUUCUUAGCAUGACAACCAGUGAAAAUGUCUCAAACGCAAAUCUGAAGACAUCUCCUCUUGGUCAAAAAACCUUCAAGGCUUCACAUCACCCAUUUGACAAAAUGAUUGGCAAGCUCCCAGCCCAUCCCAGAUUCUGCCUUCUGCCUCUGACUCUCCAGCUCACCUUUUGCUAGGCUCUUUCUUUCUCUCUCCCCCCACACAUUUAAUUUAUUUCAGUCCUUUCGGACAUCAGGCCUUCUCACAGGUGCCCAAAUACCUGUAACAUUCCCUGCCUUUGCCAGGCACUGUCAUCCUUCCUUGUUCAGUCCCUGUGCCAUGUCCUUGGCAGGAACGUCUCUGAACCCUGUCUAGGCUACAGUGGGUUCCUCUGCUGUUUAUUUACAUACAAUGCUUGCCAUUUCAAAAUAAUGGUAAUAUUUUAUUCUAAUCAUUUGAUUAAUGCUCUUCUAAUUUUAUGAUGGGAAGUUCAUGUCUGUCAGGCCUCUGAGCCCAAGCUAAUCCAUCAUAUCCCCUGUGACCUGCACGUAUACAUCCAGAUGGCCUGAAGCAACUGAAGAUCAACAAAAGUGAAAAUAGCAGGUUCCUGCCUUAACUGAUGACAUUCCACUGUUGUGAUUUGUUCCUGCCCCACCCUAACCGAUCAAUUGACUUUGUGACAAUACACCCUCCCUGCCCUUGCGAUAAUGUACUUUGUGAUAUUUCCCCACCCUUGUGAAUGCACUUUGUAUGAUACACCCUCCCCACCCUUGAGAAGGUACUUUGUAAUAUCCUUCCCUGCCCUUAAGGUACUUUGUAAUAUUCUCCUCGCCCUUGAGAAUGUACUUUGUAAGAUCCAUCCCCUGCCCACAAAAAAUUGUUCCUACUCCACCGCCUAUCCCAAACCUCUAAGAACUAAUUAUAAUCCCACCACCCUUUGCUGACUCUCUUUUCAGACUCGGCCCGCCUGUACCCAGGUGAUUAAAAAGCUUUAUUGCUCACACAAA